CAACCAGACGCCCAGUCACAGGCGAGAGCCCUGGGAUGCACCGGCCAGAGGCCAUGCUGCUGCUGCUCACGCUUGCCCUCCUGGGGGGCCCCACCUGGGCAGGGAAGAUGUAUGGCCCUGGAGGAGGCAAGUAUUUCAGCACCACUGAAGACUACGACCAUGAAAUCACAGGGCUGCGGGUGUCUGUAGGUCUUCUCCUGGUGAAAAGUGUCCAGGUGAAACUUGGAGACUCCUGGGACGUGAAACUGGGAGCCUUAGGUGGGAAUACCCAGGAAGUCACCCUGCAGCCAGGCGAAUACAUCACAAAAGUCUUUGUCGCCUUCCAAGCUUUCCUCCGGGGUAUGGUCAUGUACACCAGCAAGGACCGCUAUUUCUAUUUUGGGAAGCUUGAUGGCCAGAUCUCCUCUGCCUACCCCAGCCAAGAGGGGCAGGUGCUGGUGGGCAUCUAUGGCCAGUAUCAACUCCUUGGCAUCAAGAGCAUUGGCUUUGAAUGGAAUUAUCCACUAGAGGAGCCGACCACUGAGCCACCAGUUAAUCUCACAUACUCAGCAAACUCACCCGUGGGUCGCUAGGGUGGGGUAUGGGGCCAUCCGAGCUGAGGCCAUCUGGGUGGUGGUGGCUGAUGGUACUGGAGUAACUGAGUCGGGACGCUGAAUCUGAAUCCACCAAUAAAUAAAGGUUCUGCAGAA